CAUCAGCACUGGGCUCCGGGCUGUGCAGGGGAGUCAGACCGGCCCCCCCACCGCCCCCGUGCUGGGGCCAGCUCUCUUGGUAGAUCUUGGUAGAGGGGCGGGAUCCUGUCAGCCAAGGGCAGUCCCCCUUCCUGGAGCCUCUCCCCUCUGGCAUCUCUGUACCCCCAGGGCACUGGGAUCGAAGGCCACAACCCCUGGUCUGUAGACACCAGAACAGGGAGGAGUCCCUGGCUGAGGUUGGGGGUAAACUGAGAAAAAUGACAAGCCACCCUCUUCAACACACCACAGUUGGGCUGGGGGGGUGGAGCCCUGGCCUGGGGAGGCCGCCCACAAUUACCACAGUUUGGGAGUUUGUUAGUUCCCACCCCUGUAAGACUUGACACGUAGUCUUCAUUUCUGGGGAAUUGGCUUAAAGGGGCAGCAUCACCCAAAACCUGGGCACUUGGCUAAACCCCCACCUCUGUUAUGGGGGCCCCUUCCCCAGGAGAGGGGAGGCUGUGCCCCAUGACAGCAGAGCUUGGACCCAUCUGCAUUCUUAGGGACGCUUAGAGCAUGGUUUGGUCCUUAUUACAACCUGGGGGUGGAGGAAAGCAGCAGCUCUUCUGUCUAGUCCCCAUUCAGAGAGGGACAGGGGCUGGCCUGUGGUCACACAGCCACAGGUCACAUAGGUAGGUAUCUGCCCACCUAACGAAGGUAACCAGGGAAUGCACCAGGUGUGAUCCUUAAAGUCGAGGUACUUUUCAUCUUUCAAAAUGCAUUCGUUGGCCAGGUGUGGUGGCUCACGCCUGUAAUUUCAGCACUUUGGGAGGCCGAAGUGGGCAGAUCACCUGAGGUGAGGAGUUCAAGACCAGCCUGGCUAACAUGGUGAAACCCCAUCUCUACUAAACAAACAAAAAUUAGCCGGGCAUGGUGGUGCACACCUGUAAUCCCAGGUACUCAGGAGGCUGAGGCAGGAGAAUCACUUGAACCCGGGAGGCGGAGGUUGCAGUGAGUCGAGAUCAUACCACUGCACUACAGCCUGGGCGACAGAGCAAGAUUCCAUCUCAAAAAAAAUGCAUUAUUCUUCUCUUAUCUUUGUCCAUGACAUAAGCAGGACAGCUUAAGUUAUAGAGGGAGGACGUGAAGCCCAGAGAAAGAUGGGACUUGCCUGAGGUCACACAGCAGGUCACAGAACUGUGGUGGGGACCUGGCUGUGCUGCCUCCAGCCUCUCUGCUGUAGCACACCUACCCUUCACUGUUCCAAGGAGAGCUCGACCUCAAAGGUGUGUGCCACGGACCACAAUGUGGACAACACCACAGAGAUGCUGCAGGAGUGGCUGGCGGCUGUGGGCGAUGACUAUGCUGCUGUGGUCUGGAGGCCUGAGGGCGAGCCCAGGUUCUACCCAGAUGAAGAGGGUCCCAAGCACUGGACCAAAGAAAGGCACCAGUUUCUGAUGGAGCUGAAGCAGGAAGCCCUCACCUUUGCCAGGAACUGGGGGGCCGACUAUAUCCUGUUUGCAGACACAGACAACAUUCUGACCAACAAUCAGACUCUGCGGCUUCUCAUGGGGCAGGGGCUUCCAGUGGUGGCCCCAAUGCUGGACUCCCAGACCUACUACUCCAACUUCUGGUGUGGGAUCACCCCCCAGGGCUACUACCGCCGCACAGCCGAGUACUUCCCCACCAAGAACCGCCAGCGCCGGGGCUGCUUCCGUGUCCCCAUGGUCCACUCCACCUUCCUUGCAUCCCUGCGGGCUGAAGGGGCAGACCAGCUUGCUUUCUACCCGCCACAUCCCAACUACACUUGGCCUUUCGACGACAUCAUCGUCUUCGCCUAUGCCUGCCAGGCUGCUGGGGUCUCCGUCCACGUGUGCAAUGAGCACCGUUAUGGGUACAUGAAUGUGCCGGUGAAAUCCCACCAGGGGCUGGAAGACGAGAGGGUCAACUUCAUCCACCUGAUCUUAGAAGCACUAGUGGACGGCCCCCGCAUGCAGGCCUCAGCUCAUGUGACUCGGCCCUCUAAGAGGCCCAGCAAGAUAGGGUUUGACGAGGUCUUUGUCAUCAGCCUGGCUCGCAGGCCUGACCGUCGGGAACGCAUGCUCGCCUCGCUCUGGGAGAUGGAGAUCUCUGGGAGGGUGGUGGACGCUGUGGAUGGCUGGAUGCUCAACAGCAGUGCCAUCAGGAACCUCGGCGUAGACCUGCUCCCGGGCUACCAGGACCCUUACUCGGGCCGCACUCUGACCAAGGGCGAGGUGGGCUGCUUCCUCAGCCAUUACUCCAUCUGGGAAGAGGUGGUUGCCAGGGGCCUGGCCCGGGUCCUGGUGUUUGAGGAUGACGUGCGCUUUGAGAGCAACUUCAGGGGGCGGCUGGAGCGGCUGAUGGAGGAUGUGGAGGCAGAGAAACUGUCUUGGGACCUGAUCUACCUCGGACGGAAGCAGGUGAACCCUGAGAAGGAGACGGCCGUGGAGGGGCUGCCGGGCCUGGUGGUGGCUGGGUACUCCUACUGGACGCUGGCCUAUGCCCUGCGUCUGGCGGGUGCCCGCAAGCUGCUGGCCUCACAGCCUCUGCGCCGCAUGCUGCCCGUGGACGAGUUCCUGCCCAUCAUGUUCGACCAGCACCCCAACGAGCAGUACAAGGCACACUUCUGGCCACGGGACCUGGUGGCCUUCUCCGCCCAGCCCCUGCUCGCUGCCCCUACCCACUAUGCCGGGGACGCCGAGUGGCUCAGUGACACGGAGACAUCCUCUCCAUGGGAUGAUGACAGCGGCCGCCUCAUCAGCUGGAGCGGCUCCCAAAAGACCCUGCGCAGCCCCCGCCUGGACCUGACUGGCAGCAGCGGGCACAGCCUCCAACCCCAGCCCCGAGAUGAGCUCUAGGUCCAGGUGAUGACUGCAAAGCAGUGUCCAGGAGCAGGCCACUACUGCCCAGAGAGCAGAGGAGGAGGUUGUUGGCAGGGACUGCAGAUCCUGUCAGACCUGGCCACCACCUUGGGCAUGGCCACUCUGCCCUCUGGACCUGUCUUUCAUCGGGAGAAACCACUCAGAGAUGGAUCCCAUUCCCUAAAGGUCUCACAGCAAAGGAGCAGGACUCCCAGGCCCCUGUACCCUGCCUGGCCUGAUUCAGGGCCUUGUGGCCCCCAGCUUCUGUUUCAAGCUGGGCAGACCCCAGGAUCCCUUCCCUCCCUAAGGACUCAGCUGAGGGGCCCCUCUGCCCCCUUCUACCUCCACCUCAGCACCCUCCCCCAGCUUGAUGUUUGGGUCUCCCCAGCACCCUCCUCCCUGGCCGGUGCAAAGUACAGGGAGGUAAAGCAGGACCCUUGCAGACAUGUUGCCCAGCACACAGUAGGCCCUCAAUAAAAGCCAUUUGCACUUUAAAUAUA